GCUAGUCACCGGCCCCUGCUCAAGAAUGCCAGUGUGUGUGUAGCCUCCACAGAGAGGUCGUUUUCUCGGAGUCCAGAGGGGCCGCCUGAGCUUCUGAGAACUAGGGAGGAGCCAUCCCAGCCAUGAGCCCCUGUGGGAAUCUGCUGGGGGCCAAGUGGCCUGGAGUCCUCAGGCUCCCGCAGCUGCUCCGGAGGGAGAGGUGAGCUCAGGGCAGCCUGCCUGCAGCCAGAGGUGCCGGGAGCCCCGGGCCUGUCAUGGUGGCCAUCUACAGCCGGCCUGAGGCAGUCACAGACGGAUUUGCAGCUGAGCCUGUCUAUCUGGUGUGGGAAGAAGAUGGGGAGUUACUUGUCAGUCCCGGCUUACUUCACCUCCAGAGACCUGUUUCGGUGUUCAGAAUGCCAGGAUUCCCUCACCAACUGGUACUAUGAGAAGGAUGGGAAGCUCUACUGCCCCAAGGACUACUGGGGGAAGUUUGGGGAGUUCUGUCAUGGGUGCUCCCUGCUGAUGACAGGGCCUUUUAUGGUGGCUGGGGAGUUCAAGUACCACCCAGAGUGCUUUGCCUGUAUGAGCUGCAAGGUGAUCAUUGAGGAUGGGGAUGCAUAUGCACUGGUGCAGCAUGCCACCCUCUACUGUGGGAAGUGCCACAAUGAGGUGGUGCUGGCACCCAUGUUUGAGAGACUCUCCACAGAGUCUGUUCAGGAGCAGCUGCCCUACUCUGUCACGCUCAUCUCCAUGCCGGCCACCACUGAAGGCAGGCGGGGCUUCUCCGUGUCCGUGGAGAGUGCCUGCUCCAACUACGCCACCACUGUGCAAGUGAAAGAGGUCAACCGGAUGCACAUCAGUCCCAACAAUCGAAACGCCAUCCACCCUGGGGACCGCAUCCUGGAGAUCAAUGGGACCCCCGUCCGCACACUUCGAGUGGAGGAGGUGGAGGAUGCAAUUAGCCAGACGAGCCAGACACUUCAGCUGUUGAUUGAACAUGACCCCGUCUCCCAACGCCUGGACCAGCUGCGGCUGGAGGCCCGGCUCGCUCCUCACAUGCAGAAUGCCGGACACCCCCACGCCCUCAGCACCCUGGACACCAAGGAGAAUCUGGAGGGGACACUGAGGAGACGUUCCCUAAGGCGCAGUAACAGUAUCUCCAAGUCCCCUGGCCCCAGCUCCCCAAAGGAGCCCCUGCUGUUCAGCCGUGACAUCAGCCGCUCAGAAUCCCUUCGUUGUUCCAGCAGCUAUUCACAGCAGAUCUUCCGGCCCUGUGACCUAAUCCAUGGGGAGGUCCUGGGGAAGGGCUUCUUUGGGCAGGCUAUCAAGGUGACACACAAAGCCACGGGCAAAGUGAUGGUCAUGAAAGAGUUAAUUCGAUGUGAUGAGGAGACCCAGAAAACUUUUCUGACUGAGGUGAAAGUGAUGCGCAGCCUGGACCACCCCAAUGUGCUCAAGUUCAUUGGUGUGCUGUACAAGGAUAAGAAGCUGAACCUCCUGACAGAGUACAUUGAGGGGGGCACACUGAAGGACUUUCUGCGCAGUAUGGAUCCGUUCCCCUGGCAGCAGAAGGUCAGGUUUGCCAAAGGAAUCGCCUCCGGAAUGGCCUAUUUGCACUCUAUGUGCAUCAUCCACCGGGAUCUGAACUCGCACAACUGCCUCAUCAAGUUGGACAAGACUGUGGUGGUGGCAGACUUUGGGCUGUCACGGCUCAUAGUGGAAGAGAGGAAAAGGGCCCCCAUGGAGAAGGCCACCACCAAGAAACGCACCUUGCGCAAGAACGACCGCAAGAAGCGCUACACGGUGGUGGGAAACCCCUACUGGAUGGCCCCUGAGAUGCUGAACGGAAAGAGCUAUGAUGAGACGGUGGAUAUCUUCUCCUUUGGGAUCGUUCUCUGUGAGAUCAUUGGGCAGGUGUAUGCAGAUCCUGACUGCCUUCCCCGAACACUGGACUUUGGCCUCAACGUGAAGCUUUUCUGGGAGAAGUUUGUUCCCACAGAUUGUCCCCCGGCCUUCUUCCCGCUGGCCGCCAUCUGCUGCAGACUGGAGCCUGAGAGCAGACCAGCAUUCUCGAAAUUGGAGGACUCCUUUGAGGCCCUCUCCCUGUACCUGGGGGAGCUGGGCAUCCCGCUGCCUGCAGAGCUGGAGGAGUUGGACCACACUGUGAGCAUGCAGUACGGCCUGACCCGGGACUCACCUCCCUAGCCCUGGCCCAGCCCCCUGCAGGGGGGUGUUCUACAGCCAGCAUUGCCCCUCUGUGCCCCAUUCCUGCUGUGAGCAGGGCCGUCCGGGCUUCCUGUGGAUUGGCGGAAUGUUUAGAAGCAGAACAAGCCAUUCCUAUUACCUCCCCAGGAGGCAAGUGGGCGCAGCACCAGGGAAAUGUAUCUCCACAGGUUCUGGGGCCUAGUUACUGUCUGUAAAUCCAAUACUUGCCUGAAAGCUGUGAAGAAGAAAAAAACCCCUGGCCUUUGGGCCAGGAGGAAUCUGUUACUCGAAUCCACCCAGGAACUCCCUGGCAGUGGAUUGUGGGAGGCUCUUGCUUACACUAAUCAGCGUGACCUGGACCUGCUGGGCAGGAUCCCAGGGUGAACCUGCCUGUGAACUCUGAAGUCACUAGUCCAGCUGGGUGCAGGAGGACUUCAAGUGUGUGGACGAAAGAAAGACUGAUGGCUCAAAGGGUGUGAAAAAGUCAGUGAUGCUCCCCCUUUCUACUCCAGAUCCUGUCCUUCCUGGAGCAAGGUUGAGGGAGUAGGUUUUGAAGAGUCCCUUAAUAUGUGGUGGAACAGGCCAGGAGUUAGAGAAAGGGCUGGCUUCUGUUUACCUGCUCACUGGCUCUAGCCAGCCCAGGGACCACAUCAAUGUGAGAGGAAGCCUCCACCUCAUGUUUUCAAACUUAAUACUGGAGACUGGCUGAGAACUUACGGACAACAUCCUUUCUGUCUGAAACAAACAGUCACAAGCAAAGGAAGAGGCUGGGGGACUAGAAAGAGGCCCUGCCCUCUAGAAAGCUCAGAUCUUGGCUUCUGUUACUCAUACUCGGGUGGGCUCCUUAGUCAGAUGCCUAAAACAUUUUGCCUAAAGCUCGAUGGGUUCUGGAGGACAGUGUGGCUUGUCACAGGCCUAGAGUCUGAGGGAGGGGAGUGGGAGUCUCAGCAAUCUCUUGGUCUUGGCUUCAUGGCAACCACUGCUCACCCUUCAACAUGCCUGGUUUAGGCAGCAGCUUGGGCUGGGAAGAGGUGGUGGCAGAGUCUCAAAGCUGAGAUGCUGAGAGAGAUAGCUCCCUGAGCUGGGCCAUCUGACUUCUACCUCCCAUGUUUGCUCUCCCAACUCAUUAGCUCCUGGGCAGCAUCCUCCUGAGCCACAUGUGCAGGUACUGGAAAACCUCCAUCUUGGCUCCCAGAGCUCUAGGAACUCUUCAUCACAACUAGAUUUGCCUCUUCUAAGUGUCUAUGAGCUUGCACCAUAUUUAAUAAAUUGGGAAUGGGUUUGGGGUAUUAAUGCAAUGUGUGGUGGUUGUAUUGGAGCAGGGGGAAUUGAUAAAGGAGAGUGGUUGCUGUUAAUAUUAUCUUAUCUAUUGGGUGGUAUGUGAAAUAUUGUACAUAGACCUGAUGAGUUGUGGGACCAGAUGUCAUCUCUGGUCAGAGUUUACUUGCUAUAUAGACUGUACUUAUGUGUGAAGUUUGCAAGCUUGCUUUAGGGCUGAGCCCUGGACUCCCAGCAGCAGCACAGUUCAGCAUUGUGUGGCUGGUUGUUUCCUGGCUGUCCCCAGCAAGUGUAGGAGUGGUGGGCCUGAACUGGGCCAUUGAUCAGACUAAAUAAAUUAAGCAGUUAACAUAACUGGCAA